AGUCUUCCCUCUUCCCUUCGAGGGCCGGAAGGGGUUAAAUCUCAGGCUCCGGCGUCUGGGGAGAAGGUGAGGCGGGUAGGUAAGAGGUGAAGGAGUGCAGACUGGGUGCAAAAGAGGUGUGGCGGGAGAGAGUUCGUUUCUCUCCUGCUGGAGCGGCUUUGUUAGCAAAGGAGGGGUGAGUGGGAAGUUUGUUGCACCUGACCGAAGGGGGAAGGGCUUGCUUGGCGAAAACUGAGGCUUGAGGUUAGAUCUCGGGAUGAACUUUUCAAGAGUCCACAGUAGAUUCCAGAGCUGAAUGUUUCAGAAGCCCAGUGAAGUGUGAUCACCUCUUUCUCCGUAAAUCCACACCCCCAGCCCCACGCCGCGUUACGAAUGACACCCUUCGUUAUAAUUAUUCAAUAUGUUCCCACUGACUGAGGAAAACAAGCAUGUGGCCCAGUUGUUGCUCAAUACUGGUACUUGUCCAAGAUGUAUCUUCAGAUUCUGUGGUGUGGAUUUUCAUGCACCUUACAAACUUCCAUACAAGGAGUUGCUCAAUGAACUACAGAAAUUUCUGGAAACUGAAAAAGAUGAAUUAAUUUUGGAAGUUAUGAACCCACCUCCCAAGAAAAUUCGACUGCAAGAACUGGAAGAUAGUAUUGAUAAUCUAAGUCAAAAUGGAGAGGGAAGGAUCUCUGUUAGUCAUGUUGGAAGCACUGCUUCCAAGAACUCAAAUUUAAAUGUAUGUAAUGUAUGCCUAGGAAUUCUUCAAGAAUUCUGUGAGAAAGAUUUCAUUAAAAAGGUGUGCCAAAAGGUUGAGGCCUCUGGGUUUGAAUUCACCAGCUUGGUAUUUUCAGUCUCCUUCCCACCACAACUAUCUGUAAGAGAGCAUGCUGCAUGGUUGCUGGUAAAACAGGAAAUGGGAAAGCAGAGUCUGUCGCUGGGAAGAGAUGAUAUAGUUCAGCUAAAAGAAGCCUACAAAUGGAUAACUCACCCCCUGUUUUCAGAGGAACUGGGUGUUCCCAUUGAUGGAAAGAGCUUGUUUGAAGUGAGUGUGGUCUUUGCUCACCCAGAAACAGUUGAGGAUUGCCACUUCCUAGCUGCGAUAUGCCCAGAUUGUUUUAAGCCAGCCAAAAACAAACAGUCUGUAUUCACUAGAAUGGCAGUUAUGAAAGCCUUGAAUAAGAUAAAGGAAGAGGAUUUCCUUAAGCAGUUUCCUUGUCCUCCAAACUCACCAAAGGCUGUAUGCGCUGUUCUUGAAAUUGAAUGUGCUCAUGGUGCUGUUUUUGUGGCUGGGAGAUAUAAUAAAUACUCCAGGAAUCUACCACAAACUCCUUGGAUAAUUGAUGGAGAAAGGAAGCUGGAAUCUUCAGUGGAAGAAUUAAUUUCAGAUCAUCUGUUGGCAGUAUUUAAAGCAGAGAGUUUUAAUUUUUCAUCCUCUGGAAGAGAAGAUGUAGAUGUGAGAACAUUAGGAAAUGGAAGGCCCUUUGCAAUUGAGCUGGUGAAUCCUCAUAGAGUACAUUUCACUUCACAAGAAAUUAAGGAACUUCAGCAGAAAAUUAAUAACUCAUCUAACAAAAUCCAAGUACGUGACUUGCAGCUUGUCACAAGAGAGGCAAUAGGACAUAUGAAAGAAGGUGAAGAAGAAAAGACAAAGACCUACAGUGCCUUAAUUUGGACAAAUAAAGCGAUACAGAAGAAAGACAUUGAAUUCCUAAAUGACAUAAAGGACUUAAAAAUCGACCAGAAAACACCUUUGCGCGUCCUUCACCGAAGGCCCCUGGCUGUGCGAGCUCGCGUCAUUCACUUCAUGGAGACACAGUACGUGGAUGAGCACCACUUCCGCCUCCACUUGAAAACUCAGGCUGGCACCUACAUUAAAGAGUUUGUACAUGGAGACUUCGGGAGAACCAAGCCAAACAUUGGGUCCCUGAUGAAUGUGACUGCAGACAUUCUGGAGCUGGAUGUUGAGUCUGUAGAUGUUGACUGGCCACCUGCUCUGGAUGACUAGCUUUCAAAUUUGGAGACAAAGAGUAUGGUUUUCCUGGCAUGAUGUGGACAUCCAUGGAGCACAUGCCGUAAAAUGGCUGUUUACCCACCAUAACGGUGUCUUGAAAACUAUUUGGAUCAUGUUGAUCUAUAUAAUUGUUAAUUUGUUGUAACAUCUCAGGAUCUAUAUAUGUGUAUAUUUUGUGUUAAAUUGUUCCAAGGAUGUCUUAGGAUUUUUCUCAUUCCCUCUUUCACCCCCACAAACCAAACUAUGAAUAAUGAAAUAAUUCUCCUUAAUUCUUUCAUUUAGAGAGGUGCACAAACAGGACACAUUCUCUGUUAACCUAAGAAGCUGUAAUUUCAGCAAGAUUUCCCUCCACAAGAGAUAUACCACCUUUAAAAUCAUGUUCUAAUUUUUGUAAAUUAUCUGAAUAAAAGUUAUAUCUAGAUUUAUGCAGCAUAAUAUCCUAUAAUAGUCUAAGAUUGCAAAUGCAAAUCUGACAUCAUUAUUUUCCCCAGGAAGCCUCAAACAAGCUAUUACCAAUGAAGUUCUUUUGGCUGUGAUUUGUCAUAAAUCUUAACCAAACUAUGAAUAAUGAAAUAAUUCUCAUUAAUACUUUCAUUAAGAAAGAAUUUUGACAAUCUAAAAUUGUCAAUAUAGGUUUCCUGUGGAGGGAAAGUAAAACCGUAGGAGCCAAGGCAUGCCAUGGUAGGAGCCUUUCAUAAAUCUUUUAAAUAAGGAGAAACAAGUGCCUUUAAUAACUUCAAUCCCAGGGUUAAGAAUUUGAAAAAUUGAGAUUGCUAAACAAAGACGAACUGGUAUUAUUUCAGAAUGCUUCAAUAUAUUAUCCAAUUAUAAACAUUUUAAUAAUACCUUAUUAAAGUAGAUAGGAUAUUGUCUCCAUUUUAUAAAUAUGGAAACCAAAGACUAGAAGUUAAAUGACUUAUCCAAAAUUGUUAGCUACUUCUAUAUUGAGGACUAGAACUGAAGUUUCUUGGUUUCUAGGGUCUUUCUAAUAAGCCCUAUUACUGAGCACCUGUUUGUGUGAAGGGGCAGCUAUGGAUGCCAUUUAAACUCAUGUAACUGAUAAUUAACUUUUGGAAUGUAGUUACCAAAUCAAAGAGCUUACCAAAAAAUAGCCCAAGACUAUUUAAUACAAUCUUAUAUAGUUACCAUUUGUUAUUAAGUUAAACCUCAGUUGGUAUUAUGAAGAGGAAAAACAUUAAGCUAAACCUAAAAAAAAUGAAUGGGUCAUUUAAGUUUCAGAAAGGAGCCUCAUUACAAUUUCAGAUUUGAGUAUAAUUUCCAUCACCCUAAUUCAACUAUUUGAGCUUUUUUUAAGAAUACAUGUGACUUGACUAGUAUUAGAUUACUAACCAUUUCCCAUCUCUAUAUUAAACAUAAAUCACAGAUACCAAGAUUCACUUUAGAUAUGAGGAAAAUGGUUUUAAUGGACACAAAGGAGUCAGCCACGUUGGAACCAACAUAGUUUCAUACCACGUUGAAACCAUGUGUUUGAUAUGCAAAUAACAGCAAAUAAUUUUUUCACUCUUGUCAAUGCCAAUGCAUUGAAAGGCCCAGAAAAUGAGAAAAGGAUAACAAACUUUUGAUAAAAAGGUAAGAAUUUCUGUGUGGAUGUUCCUCAGUUUCUGGGAAAAUUUUGCUACAAAAGAGAUUUAAAUAAUUUAGGAGGCAGUCUUUUGCAUGGUAUUUUUGGCUUACCUUUGAAUCUAGUGGACCUGUAAUAUGUAAGAAUGAAGAAUGUGCUUAGCAAACUGAAAUGAGAAGAUUUCUAUUUCUUAAAUUUCUAUUCCUGAGAUUAUAUAAAAUUUCACGCAAAGAGUAAGCAUUAGCUUUAAAUACUUCUUCCAAAUGUUCCUAGAAUUUUGAGACAAAGAUUGUUAAAAAUUAAUGUAUGUCUUUGUUUUAGGCAGAACUGGAAAUAUUAAGUAGUGAGAGUACUAUAGUUUCCCUUUUGCCUACAUAAAAGCAUUUUAAAAUUAGUUUUAUGAUUUCUUUGUAAGCUUUAUUUAAAUUCAAAGUCUUUUUCAUAACACUUAAGAGAAAGAGCCCUUUGUACUUCUUAGUAUCUCUUAUAUAGUCCCAAAUAUAGUCUGUGGUUUAUUUUAGGAAAAACAUCAACUCUGAAUACCUGGAAAAGUCAAAAGAAAAUAAAGUUGGUAAAAUGAAAAA